CCUAUCAUCGCAAAACUCAUGAUGCUCCGGCUGCUCAGUUCCCUCCUCCUUGUGGCCGUUGCCUCAGGCUAUGGCCCACCUUCCUCUCGCCCUUCCAGCCGCGUUGUCAAUGGUGAGGAUGCGGUCCCCUACAGCUGGCCCUGGCAGGUUUCCCUGCAGUAUGAGAAAAGCGGAAGCUUCUACCACACCUGUGGCGGUAGCCUCAUCGCCCCCGACUGGGUUGUGACUGCCGGCCACUGCAUCUCGAGCUCCCGGACCUACCAGGUGGUGUUGGGCGAGUACGACCGUGCUGUGAAGGAGGGCCCCGAGCAGGUGAUCCCCAUCAACUCUGGGGACCUCUUUGUGCAUCCACUCUGGAACCGCUCGUGUGUGGCCUGUGGCAAUGACAUCGCCCUCAUCAAGCUCUCACGCAGCGCCCAGCUGGGAGACGCCGUCCAGCUCGCCUCACUCCCUCCGGCUGGUGACAUCCUUCCCAACGAGACACCCUGCUACAUCACCGGCUGGGGCCGUCUCUAUACCAACGGGCCACUCCCAGACAAGCUGCAGGAGGCCCUGCUGCCGGUGGUGGACUAUGAACACUGCUCCAGGUGGAACUGGUGGGGUUCCUCCGUGAAGAAGACCAUGGUGUGUGCUGGAGGGGACAUCCGCUCCGGCUGCAAUGGUGACUCUGGAGGACCCCUCAACUGCCCCACAGAGGAUGGUGGCUGGCAGGUCCAUGGCGUGACCAGCUUUGUUUCUGCCUUUGGCUGCAACACCCGCAGGAAGCCCACGGUGUUCACUCGAGUCUCCGCCUUCAUUGACUGGAUUGAGGAGGGGCUGUGCAGAAUGGAAACCACACUUGCCUGUCUCCCAGGAAGCCAGAAACUACAGGGCAACAAGGCACCAGAGUCCCGGACUUAGGACCACUGUGUGUGAUUCACCGUGAACACUGGCAUAUUAAAGGCUCUGAGAAGUCCUGUAGGAAAGGACAAUUUGAACUUUGUUUGAGCUCAUAUUUUCCAAUCCCAUCUGACCUUUAGUUCUUCACUGAGUGCCCACUGGGUUAUAUUCUGGGAGCCGAGGCCACAGCAGUGAACAAAGCACACAAAACCCCCCGCCCCAUGGGGGCUCCGUUCUAGUGGGUCCAUUUAUCAUCAAACAUCUAUUAAUAUCUCUAGAAUGUGCCCAUCAGGACACCAUCCAGAUGCUGCUGCGCUUUUCCAGGCCACACAGAGGGGACACCCUCCAGGUGCAUCCUGCAUGAAUAUCAGGCUCAACCGUGCUUUCAGGGUAGGAAGCGGAGGGCAUUUGAAGAGUCCUUUCCCUUCCUUCAUUCAUUUGUUGUCUCCUUGAAUAAAUGCUGUUGAAAACCUA